GUUUGAGUACUGGGCAGGCAGCAGGGAGAGUCAGGCAGCAGCUGUGAGCGGGUGGCUCUUCCCCACCUUGCCAGCAGGCUCUGUGCUCCUUGAAGCAAGCGCUCCAGAGGCUCCGGAAGCCACGGCUGGAUUGGAGACAAGAUGGGAUCCUCAGAGGACCAGGCCUAUCGCCUCCUUAAUGACUACGCCAACGGCUUCAUGGUGUCCCAGGUUCUCUUCGCCGCCUGCGAGCUGGGCGUGUUUGACCUUCUCGCCGAGGCCCCAGGGCCCCUGGACGUGGCGGCAGUGGCUGCAGGUGUGAGGGCCAGCGCCCAUGGGACAGAGCUCCUGCUGGACAUCUGUGUGUCCCUGAAGCUGCUGAAAGUGGAGACGAGGGGAGGAAAAGCUUUCUAUCGAAACACAGAGCUGUCCAGCGACUACCUGACCACGGUCAGCCCGACGUCACAAUGCAGCAUGCUGAAGUACAUGGGCAGGACCAGCUACCGGUGCUGGGGCCACCUGGCAGACGCCGUGAGAGAAGGAAGGAACCAGUACCUGGAGACGUUUGGCGUUCCCGCUGAAGAGCUUUUUACGGCCAUCUACAGGUCCGAGGGCGAGCGGCUACAGUUCAUGCAAGCUCUGCAGGAGGUCUGGAGCGUCAACGGGAGAAGCGUGCUGACCGCCUUUGACCUGUCAGUGUUCCCACUUAUGUGUGACCUUGGUGGGACAUGGAUAAAGCUGGAAACCAUCAUUCUCAGCAAACUAUCGCAAGGACAGAAAACCAAACACCGCGUGUUCUCACUCAUAGGUGGGGCUGGAGCUCUGGCUAAGGAAUGCAUGUCUCUGUACCCUGGAUGUAAGAUCACCGUUUUUGACAUCCCAGAAGUGGUGUGGACGGCAAAGCAGCACUUCUCAUUCCAGGAGGAAGAACAGAUUGACUUCCAGGAAGGGGAUUUCUUCAAAGACCCUCUUCCGGAAGCUGAUCUGUACAUCCUGGCCAGGGUCCUCCAUGACUGGGCAGACGGAAAGUGCUCACACCUGCUGGAGAGGAUCUACCACACUUGCAAGCCAGGUGGUGGCAUUCUGGUAAUUGAAAGCCUCCUGGAUGAAGACAGGCGAGGUCCUCUGCUCACGCAGCUCUACUCUCUGAACAUGCUUGUGCAGACGGAAGGGCAGGAGAGGACCCCCACCCACUACCACAUGCUCCUCUCUUCUGCUGGCUUCAGAGACUUCCAGUUUAAGAAAACAGGAGCCAUUUAUGAUGCCAUUUUAGCCAGGAAAUAACUGUUUCUUGUGACCUGGAACUAACGUCAAAGCACACAAGACAUAAUAAUAAAGACAUGUACCUCCA